AUGUCCAGCUGGGCUGUGGGGAAUCUUCCAGGCCUGUUACCUGUAUGCUGCCUGGUGACACCUGGUGGAUUUCACGGGGACUGCCAUGGCACCUACGGAGUACAGUCCGGCCCUGACAGUCAACAGGUUGAGAAGCCUGAUCUAGCUGUGGCAGGGAAGACAGAUACCAGAGAAACUAACAAUGAAAACGGACUCGUUGAUGGAGGAAAAGUUGGAAUGCAGCCUCUGGUGCUGUUUGAGCGAUCCCUCUACCCCGGGUCGCUGCUGUGUUCUGGAAAGGCGCAUUGUACCCUGGAUGCGGCAGAAACUGUAAAGGAGGAUGUGGCUAUAGGGGCUGAUUGUUCUCAUGAGUGUUACUACUCUUCUUUCCCACAGUUAAAAGAAUAUUGGCAGAGGAAGAGCCCUGGCAUUCCAGAAGGAGCUAACAGGAAAAAGAAAAUCAAUGGCAGUAGCCCUGACACAGCCACUUCUGGUGGUUACCACUCACCUGGGGAUUCAGCAACAGGUAUCUACGGGGAGGGCCGUGCAUCAUCUGCUACCCUGGAGGAUCUGGAGAGCCAGUACCAAGAACUAGCAGUGGCCCUGGAUUCAAGCUCCACAAUAAUCAGUCAACUCACUGAAAACAUCAAUUCACUGGUAAGAGUCCAGUGGGGUCCCCUGAUUCCAGCCUGUGAAUCCUGGACUCCAGUUUCCUCUUGGGGCCCUGAAGAAAGGGGCUAG